ACUUCCGCCCGCGACCCCCUUCCAGACCCGCUCCCGAAACCUUGUCGAAGGACCAAAGGCGACCGGUGCAGGUGCACGACGCCAGCUCCCUUCUGGGGGGCCGGGGCCUGGGGGUUGCCAUGGCCCCCAGCCACCUGUCAGUGCGGGAGAUGAGGGAAGAUGAGAAGCCCCUGGUGCUGGAGAUGCUGAAGGCCGGCGUGAAGGACACGGAAAACCGCGUGGCCCUCCAUGCCUUGACACGGCCGCCGGCCCUGCUCCUCCUGGCGGCGGCCAGCAGCGGCCUGCGCUUUGUCCUGGCUUCCUUCGCCCUGGCCCUCCUCCUGCCGGUGUUCCUGGCUGUGGCCGCCGUGAAGCUGGGCCUGCGGGCCCGAUGGGGCUCGCUGCCUCCGCCGGGUGGCCUGGGGGGCCCCUGGGUGGCCGUGCGGGGCUCCGGUGACGUGUGUGGGGUCCUGGCUCUGGCCCCUGGCACAAAUGCAGGGGACGGGGCCCGGGUCACCCGCCUGUCUGUCUCUCGCUGGCACCGCCGCCGGGGCGUGGGCAGGAGGCUGCUGGCCUUCGCGGAGGCCCGGGCUCGGGCCUGGGCUGGGGGCAUGGGGGAGCCCCGGGCCCGGCUCGUGGUCCCCGUGGCUGUGGCCGCCUGGGGGGUGGGAGGGAUGCUGGAGGGCUGUGGCUACCAGGCCGAGGGGGGCUGGGGCUGCCUGGGCUACACGCUGGUGAGGGAAUUCAGCAAAGACCUGUGAAGCUACAGACUGACAGCCAGGGCAGGGGAGGAGGGAGGGGCGCCAGCACCUGAUGAUCGCCUACUGUCUGCGGGUUCUUUUACCUGCUCUCCCUCAGUGAGUCCUCAACCACCCUGGGCCCAGAAACAGAGGCCUGCCGAGGGGAGGAGCCUGGCCUCUGUCCACCCGUCAGCAGUGUGAAGUCUGUUGUGUUUGAGCUUCUCAGAGUGGAAUGACUCCUUUUCCUUCCUGGCCCUCGGGGGCCUCUCGAGGUCAGCCUCUCCAACCCCUACCUCAGCUCCUGUCUGCACUGAGAAACCUCCCCGGGUGAUGUCUGCAAAGUCUGUGCUGUCCGUGCCCCAGGCUGGGAGAGCUAUCUGGGGAGGGGGAGAGGAGGCCGAGCAGAAUACACCCCAGAGUUAGGGUUUGCGACUCCGCCUCCCUGGGACCUGGAUUGGGUCAGAUGCCUGUCCUUGGAGGGGACAAGGUUGACUGCUUAGGAGGCGCGACGCACAGGGCUGCCAGGCCUGGCCCCUCUCUGGGAAGGUUGAGAGCUGAGACGGGCAGCCCUGUCCCUUCCUCCAGAUCCGUCUGGUUUUUUACACCGUUUGUUAAUAAAGCCUGAAACCGC